AGCGUGGCUACGCCAUCACGACCGGCGGUGGCACAUGCGCAAUAGCGAGACGCUGGAGCGCGGCGUAGGUGGCUGCCGAGUCUUUUCCUGUUUAGGGUCUUAUCCUGGCAUUGAGGGCGCCGGACUGGCGCUUUUGGCCGACUUGGCAUUGGGUGGGCGGCUUCUUGGGACCCACAUGAGCCAGUGGCAUCAUCCCCGCAGUGGCUGGGGCCGGAGACGCGACUUUUCAGGACGCUCCUCAGCCAAGAAGAAGGGCGGAAACCACAUCCCCGAAAGGUGGAAAGACUAUCUCCCAGUUGGACAGCGGAUGCCUGGGACUCGUUUCAUUGCUUUCAAAGUUCCUUUGCAAAAGAGUUUUGAAAAGAAACUUGCUCCAGAAGAAUGCUUUUCCCCUUUGGAUCUUUUUAACAAAAUCCGAGAACAAAAUGAAGAACUUGGACUGAUUAUUGAUUUAACAUAUACUCAACGCUAUUAUAAACCAGAGGAUUUGCCAGAAACUGUUCCUUACUUAAAAAUUUUUACAGUUGGACAUCAAGUGCCUGAUGAUGAGACUAUUUUUAAAUUCAAACACGCUGUUAAUGGGUUUUUGAAAGAAAAUAAAGAUAAUGAUAAACUUAUUGGUGUCCACUGUACCCAUGGUUUAAACAGGACUGGCUACCUCAUUUGCAGAUAUUUGAUUGAUGUAGAAGGCGUGAGGCCAGAUGAUGCAAUUGAAUUAUUCAAUAGGUGCCGGGGACAUUGCUUAGAAAGACAAAACUACAUUGAAGACCUUCAGAAUGGUCCUAUCAGAAAGAAUUGGAAUUCCAGUGUACCCAGGUCAAGUGAUUUUGAAGACUCAGCACAUCUCAUGCAACCAGUCCACAAUAAGCCUGUUAAACAAGGACCUAGGUAUAAUCUACAUCAGAUCCAGGGUCACUCAGCUCCUCGACAUUUCCACACCCAGACCCAAAGUUUGCAACAAUCAGUCAGAAAAUUUUCAGAGAAUCCACAUGUUUACCAGAGACACCAUCUCCCUCCUCCUGGUCCCCCUGGAGAGGACUAUUCACACAGGAGGUAUUCUUGGAAUGUGAAGCCCAAUGCCAGUCGGGCAGCCCAGGAUAGAAGAAGGUGGUAUCCUUAUAAUUACUCCAGACUCUCCUAUCCAGCCUGUUGGGAAUGGACCCAGUGAUACAAACCUGUCCUGGAAUUCUACCUGGAGACCAGAGCUGGCCUGAAAAUUACUGGUGUGACUUUUAAUUAGUUCAGGUCUAAUCAGGUUUCUUUAUUGUUCCCUUAUGUAUUCAAGCUUAAGGAAAAAUUGCAUUGCUGUUUACCUCUUUGCUGAUAAAUUUGCAGUAAUUACAGCAUUGCAGGAAAAACAAUCUGUUAUUCCAGUCUUAAAUUUUUCUAAAAGAAGACAAUAUUUUAGAACUGAAGCAUUGAGAACUUCCCUUGCAAAUUAUUUUUAAAAUUCUAUCUUGUUUUUCUAUGUAUUUCUUUCUGACUAGACUUGUGAUAUGCGUGUGUUUAUGUACAGAAAUUUUUAGUGUUUUUGUUAUGUUCUGUUAUUGACCCAAAGGCCAUCUUUAUUUUCUAUAACUGUUCAAAAUUUAUAUUAAAAUCUACUUAGGAGAUAA